GCUCGCCCGCCCGCGCCUCCAGCGGAAGCCGGAAGCAAAAGCGGGUCCUGCUAGCCCCGCGGCUCCGAACUCGGUGGUCCUGGAAGCUCCGCAGGAUGGGGGAGAAGAUGGCGGAAGAGGAGAGGUUCCCCAAUACAACUCAUGAGGGUUUCAAUGUCACCCUCCACACCACCCUGGUUGUCACGACGAAACUGGUGCUCCCGACCCCUGGCAAGCCCAUCCUCCCCGUGCAGACAGGGGAGCAGGCCCAGCAAGAGGAGCAGUCCAGCGGCAUGACCAUUUUCUUCAGCCUCCUUGUCCUAGCUAUCUGCAUCAUAUUGGUGCAUUUACUGAUCCGAUACAGAUUACAUUUCUUGCCAGAGAGUGUUGCUGUUGUUUCUUUAGGUAUUCUCAUGGGAGCAGUUAUAAAAAUUAUAGAGUUUAAAAAACUGGCGAAUUGGAAGGAAGAAGAAAUGUUUCGUCCAAACAUGUUUUUCCUCCUCCUGCUUCCCCCUAUUAUCUUUGAGUCUGGAUAUUCAUUACACAAGGGUAACUUCUUUCAAAAUAUUGGUUCCAUCACCCUGUUUGCUGUUUUUGGGACGGCAAUCUCCGCUUUUGUAGUAGGUGGAGGAAUUUAUUUUCUGGGUCAGGGUUUUUUUUUUGUGUGUGUCUGUGUGUUUGUGUGUUUUAUUUUACAGGCUGAUGUAAUCUCUAAACUCAACAUGACAGACAGUUUUGCGUUUGGCUCCCUAAUAUCUGCUGUCGAUCCAGUGGCCACUAUUGCCAUUUUCAAUGCACUUCAUGUGGACCCCGUGCUCAACAUGCUGGUCUUUGGAGAAAGUAUUCUCAACGAUGCAGUCUCCAUUGUUCUGACCAAUACAGAAGAAAAAUAUGCUCCUGGGAGCUGUUGUCACCUUUCCUUGGUUAUCAGAAUCAUACCUGGUUUUGAAGAGGUAUACUUCAUAAACGAUCAUCUCCAAACUGAAGGUUUAACAAGAAAAAAUAUGUCAGAUGUCAGUGGGUGGCAAACAUUUUUACAAGCCCUUGACUACUUCCUCAAAAUGUUCUUUGGCUCUGCAGCGCUCGGCACUCUCACUGGCUUAAUUUCUGCAUUAGUGCUGAAGCAUAUUGACUUGAGGAAAACGCCUUCCUUGGAGUUUGGCAUGAUGAUCAUUUUUGCUUAUCUGCCUUAUGGGCUUGCAGAAGGAAUCUCACUCUCAGGCAUCAUGGCCAUCCUUUUCUCAGGCAUCGUGAUGUCCCACUACACGCACCAUAACCUCUCCCCAGUCACCCAGAUCCUCAUGCAGCAGACCCUCCGCACCGUGGCCUUCUUAUGUGAAACAUGUGUGUUUGCAUUUCUUGGCCUGUCCAUUUUUAGUUUUCCUCACAAGUUUGAAAUUUCCUUUGUCAUCUGGUGCAUAGUGCUUGUACUAUUUGGCAGAGCGGUAAACAUUUUCCCUCUUUCCUACCUCCUGAAUUUCUUCCGGGAUCAUAAAAUCACACCGAAGAUGAUGUUCAUCAUGUGGUUUAGUGGCCUGCGGGGAGCCAUCCCCUAUGCCCUGAGCCUACACCUGGACCUGGAGCCCAUGGAGAAGCGGCAGCUCAUCGGCACCACCACCAUCGUCAUCGUGCUCUUCACCAUCCUGCUGCUGGGCGGCAGCACCAUGCCCCUCAUUCGCCUCAUGGACAUCGAGGACGCCAAGGCACACCGCAGGAACAAGAAGGACGUCAACCUCAGCAAGACUGAGAAGAUGGGCAACACUGUGGAGUCGGAGCACCUGUCGGAGCUCACGGAGGAGGAGUACGAGGCCCACUACAUCAGGCGGCAGGACCUUAAGGGCUUCGUGUGGCUGGACGCCAAGUACCUGAACCCCUUCUUCACUCGGAGGCUGACGCAGGAGGACCUGCACCACGGGCGCAUCCAGAUGAAAACUCUCACCAACAAGUGGUACGAGGAGGUACGCCAGGGCCCCUCCGGCUCCGAGGACGACGAGCAGGAGCUGCUCUGACGCCAGGUGCCAAGGCUUCAGGCAGGCAGGCCCAGGAUGGGCGUUUGCUGCGCACAGACACUCAGCAGGGGCCUCGCAGAGAUGCGUGCAUCCAGCAGCCCCUUCAAGACAUAAGAGGGCGGGGCGAGGUACUGGCUGCAGAGUCGCCUUAGUCCAGAACCUGACAGGCCUCUGGAGCCAGGCGACUUCUUGGGAAACUGUCAUCUCCCGACUCCUCCCUGAGCCAGCCUCCGCUCAGUGUGGCUCCUCAGCCCACAGAGGGGAGGGAGCAUGGGGCCAGGUGCCAGUCAUCUGUGAAGCUAGGGCGCCUACCCCCCCACCCGGAGGACCCCUGCGGCCCCCUGCCUAGAGGAGCACCAUCUACAGUUGUGCCAUUCCCCAGCCACUGCCUUCAUGCUGCCCCCGCCGGACUGGCAGAGCCAGGGGUCAGCCACCUGCCUUUGAGUCAUCAAGAUGCCUCUGCAGCCACAAUUCUGACCUAAGUGGCAGGGCCCAGAAAUCCUGAAAACCUCCCGCUGCCUUUUGUGAUACUUCCUGUGCUCCCUCAGAGAGAAACGGAGUGACCUUUUGUCCUUUACCUGAUUGGCACUUCGCAGUCUAUCUCCCUGGGUAGCAGACGGCUGCUGCCCUUCUCUGGGCAUGUUCUGAAUGUUUACACUGGUACCUUCUGGUAUCUUCUUUAGAGCCCCCUGCAAGCUGCAACUCUAGGCUUUUAUCUUGCGGGGUCAGAGCGCCCUCUAGAGGGAAAAGCUAGAGGCACAGGGUUUCUGCCGGCCCACAACUGCUGUCUUGAUUUGCAUUUUACAGCAAAGUGCUGAGAGCCUCUAGUCGCCUCCUGCCAUCUGAUCUCCCUCCCCACCAUUCCCGUACUCAGUUGUUCUUUUGUCUAAUCGGAGGCCACUGUGCUGAGGCCCUGCAGUGUCUGCUCACUGCUGCCAUCUUCGCUGCUAGUCAGGGUUCCAUCCUCUUUCCCCUCUCCCAGUUCCCUACCACGUUGGAUCCCAUUCGUCACCCAUGCUAGGGUCCCCAAAGCACUGGGGCAGGGGCCAGAGCAGCAGCACCCAGUGCUCCCUCCUCUACUCUGACCUGGGGCCCCAGCAUCCUGGAGCACACGCUCCACGCACACACACCCCAGCCCUGUCCCAGGGGCCUGGCCCCCUCAGCCAUCUCAGGGUGAGGAGCUGCCAGUCAUGUCCAGAUGGAAUGACUCCCAUCCUCUCCUCAUCUCCCCUUUGACGAGCCUCAAACUGCUCAGCUCAUCAAAGAGCCAUUGCCAACUUCCGUAUGUGGUUCUGGGUCCCAGGGAGCCUUGGAACCUGGCACCCUGGGGUGGUUUAAUUCAUCAUUAAGAAGCAUUCCUGCUUCUCAAGGGACACAGUGGCCUGCAUGGGCCAGCAUGGACCCUGGGCUGAUCAUGUGCAUUCCUGCUUCUCUGGGGACACAGUGGGCCCACAUGGGCCAGCAUGGACCCUGGGCUAGAGCAAGCACAUCUCCAUCUCUUCCACCUCAGGCAGUGUGGCUCCAGAUGUCAGGAGGGACUGACCUCAGGACCUUCCAGGUUCCUCUGUGCCAGGAAUGAGAGGCCAGGCCCGAUCCUACCACCUCGCCUUGACCCUGAAGUCAGAGCAGGCCAGCCAAGCAGGAAGCACACUGUUUACUUUUUGCAUGAAAAGUAAAUGUGUACUUGAUAGAGCUAAAAUAUGAUCUUUUUUAAUUUCUCAACCCCAUAAUUUGAGCCAUUGCCUUGCUUAAUUUUGGUUUCCACCAUUUCCUUUUAGUGGAGAAGAGAGGAAGUCAGAGGGUAGGGACCUUUGCCUGCCCCUGGGCGAGUGCGGGCAGGGAUCUGAGACCAGAUUGUUCUCGCACCCCUGCCAGAACUCACUCUCCCCUGAAGUUUAGGGUCCCAUCUCCCAGAUGUAAGUUGUUUUGCAAACUCAGUUUGCCAGGAUUUCUUUCUUUCCUAAUCUUAAAUUCACAGAUAAAGCAAUGAAAAGAGUCAGAUCCCAUUUCCGUCUGCCCCCUCGUCACCAGGUGUGAUAGCCCCAGCCAGGUCACACCUGGCCUCACACUUUGAGCUGAGACUUGAAAACGAUGCUGUGGCGGAAGAGCAUGUGGGGCUUGGUGGAGGGGCCCCAGGAUUUGUUGGGGGCAAAGGGGGUGGCGGGACCGUUCCCAGGAGGUACCAGCACCUGCCUCGAUCUCCUCUGAGCCUCUUCUGCCCCCUGUCGGCCAGGUGAGGUCAGCAGCCUGGGAGAGUGCCCCCAAGAGAUGAGGGCACCCCGUGUUCCUUGGCAAUCUUGGCUCACCUUGGUAACAAAAGGCCAUAGAAGUCUGUUUUUCUGGGUCAGUUUUUUUUGCCUGAGAAUAACAAAUUGCUGCUGUCUACCUUUAGCACACCCAAUAAUUCUAUUUGGGGCAGUGAAUGCAUAGAAGAUAUAAAAAUACGCAGCUUAACUAUAUCUUCCUGCGUGUGUAUUUAUUUUCUUCUGGGUCUAGGCCAUGGUACAGGAGAACUGUGGCGUGUAGGAGGAAUACUUCAGGAUGAGUGAAGGCUGGAGCCAGGGAGCGCUGGAGGAAACCAGCCCUUUAGCCAGCAGCCCCUCCACCACAGGCACUGCUGUGUGGAACGAGUUCUUGGAAUGAAUCCCAUGCUUUCUGCAGCCUGUAGUUGUUAUGACCCCUCGGAACAACCACCCCGUGGCUUGUGUGGGGUCUCGCAGGGAAAAGGGCUGGCUUCUAGGUCCCCGAGAUAAGUGUGCAGGGGGAUGGGCCAGGGCCAGGCUAAGGGUGGCUCAGUUCCAUCAUCUGGAGGUCAGACACACUGUCCAGAGGCAGAACUGAAGCCCUCUCGGCCCCUACCCUAAGCCAGCCACCCCUCUUCACAGUGGGUGAGCUGGGCUGGGCUGGCUGGCAUGAGGCCAAGGGGUAGGCCUGAGCGCCAGAGUCGCCCAGGUUAGCCCACAGGAUUCCUUUGUGUGCCAUGGAAUGCUGAAAGAUGGGUGACUGGGGACCCUUCUUAAAACCUUUGGCAAAGGUGCCAUCGGCAGGGCUUGGCCUCAUGAAGUCUCAGGUCCGUGUUCCCGCAGGGCGCACAUGCUUGGAGAGUCCUCAGCAGGGUAGCCGAGGCCAGGCCACUUCUGCUGAGGAUGGGGCAGGCUGGGGUGUGGGUGUGGCCUGGGGUGGCUCAGGGCUGGAACUGCUGCCUGAUUCCUGUGUGGGGAGAAGCUCAGUGGCCGUUUGCUGCCACUGACAAGGAUUUCACAUGCAGAAGAGAAAAGGCCCCCCUCCACCCCCCGCAUUCCCUGCCGAGUGAGAGCCAGUGUUUGCUGCCCUUGCUGGGGGCGGGUAGGAAACCCUGAGCUUCCUGAUGCGGAGUCAUGAAGCAGAGUCCUCGGGAAGGCAUCUCCACAGCCCCGGGUCCUCUGUCUAACGCCCUCCAUUUCACGCCCUCCAUCUCACAGUCAAGAUAAAGGCCUCGAGAAUAAAGAGCCAGCCCCCUUCCAUUUAGUCUCCUGCCGUUUCCCAAACAGUUGUCCAACAGUUAGACAUUGAGGGGCUUCACUGUUACCAGGCAUGUAACAGAAGGAGGAAGACUAACACACACCCCCUGCCCCAUCCCAUCCCCCUCUCCCGAGCUAUUUUCUUGCUGUGGCCUCUGGUGCCCUUGAGUUGGUCUCCCCGGCUGCUCUGCGGGGGCUUCACUGGCUUCGGAGUGAGCGCGAAGUGCUGGUGAGCAGUGGGCCUGUGAUUGGAUGGGAAGAUGUGCAUCCGUGGUCAAAAGUCAGCUGCCAGCCCUGCGGAACCAGAGCCUCAGGCUGGGAUGGGGAGGCCUCCCUGCUUCCACCUGCAUGGUGGGCAUGGCCUGGCUUACACCAAAGGCUUUGACGGUUUCUCCAAGUAAGGAUCUGCAAAUCUUGAAUCGUCCUCAAAAUGACGAAGCUUGAAUUGUCCUCAAGAUGGAUGUGAAUCUUACAUUCCUUUUCAUCAUUUCCUUUGUAAAAAUGACGAGUGCUGGGUUUUUGUUUUAAGAAGCAUUAUGAAGGCCAGACUUACUCAUUUUUCUCCCCCAAGUGAGCUGCAAGAGGCCCCUGUUAGGCCCCUGUUUCCUGAGCAGUGAUGUGCUGCUCUUCUUGGUGGGGCUUUGGGCUGGGAGGGGAAGGCGGGUCAGAGAUGGGGGACCUGUGGCUGCCAUGCAGGAGCCCCUGCGUCAUCUCGUUGGACUCUUUAAGGGAGUCAGGAAUAGAUGUAUGAACAGUCGUGUCACUGGAUGCCUAUUUAGAAAUAAAGUGUAUGCUGCUGAAUUGGA